CUCCUGCGCACGCGGCCCGGUCGCUGUCGGAAGCGGCUGUGCGGGUGGCGGCCGGCGCGCGGUGGGGCAUGGCGGGUUCGCGGGGUGCGGGGCGCACGGCGGCGCCGAGCGUGCGGCCGGAGAAGCGGCGGUCUGAGCCCGAACUGGAGCCUGAGCCCGAGCCGGAGCCCCCCCUCCUCUGCACCUCUCCUCUCAGCCACAGCACCGGCAGCGAUUCUGGCGUCUCCGACAGCGAGGAAAGUGUGUUCUCAGGCCUGGAAGAUUCCGGCAGUGACAGCAGUGAGGAUGAUGACGAAGGCGACGAGGAGGGAGAGGACGGAGCCCUUGAUGACGAGGGCCACAGUGGGAUUAAAAAGACCACUGAGGAGCAGGUGCAGGCCAGCACUCCUUGCCCGAGGACAGAGAUGGCGAGCGCCCGGAUUGGGGAUGAGUAUGCGGAGGACAGCUCUGAUGAGGAGG